GUUGACUAGGCCUCGGGGGCGACGUUCAUUGACCAGGCGGCUGAGUUUCGCGGGGUCUGCGGGUUUAGGGCGCCGACGCUCUGCAAACGGCAGCGGAGGCCUUAACGCGUCGCGGCCGGGAGAAUCGGAGCGAGCCAGGCUUGAGGGCGAAUGUCCCGGGAGGACUUGUGGCGGCCCUGGUUUCGCCUCCUCCUUUCUCGUUGCAUCUUCCCCGGCGUGGGGGCAGGGGCUGGGGGUGGCAGUUGGGAGCACCGUCUCUGACACCUAGGCCCCGGGGGUGGCUCUGCCACCAAGUCGUAGGCGAGCGUAAUGAAAGCAAAGAUAGCAAAUUGUAAGGAGGGCUUUGACUUUUGUCAUCUUCUGAAUGACGCACAGCUGAUGUCAUCCUAAUUAAGCGCAUUCACUCCUAGUCUCUGGAAAUGCAAAUCAAAUAUGCGAGAUGCGGCACUGCAUUUUUAAUGUUGACCAUAAUGUAAUGAUGAAGCAAAUUUUUAUUUAAUUUUCGAGUCUGCACCUAUUUUGGCCAAGUAAAGACAGUAAAAUAGGGAGAGCCUCCUGAGGAUCUGAAUUUAUUGCCCUGGCACAUAAUUUUUAGCUCUUUCUCCCUUUGUCUCAUAACCAUGUCCACCAACGAGAAUGCUAAUACACCAGCUGCCCGUCUUCACAGAUUCAAGAACAAGGGAAAAGACAGUACAGAAAUGAGGCGUCGCAGAAUAGAGGUCAAUGUGGAGCUGAGGAAAGCUAAGAAGGAUGACCAGAUGCUGAAGAGGAGAAAUGUAAGCUCAUUUCCUGAUGAUGCUACUUCUCCGCUGCAGGAAAACCGCAACAACCAGGGCACUGUAAAUUGGUCUGUUGAUGACAUUGUCAAAGGCAUAAAUAGCAGCAAUGUGGAAAAUCAGCUCCAAGCUACUCAAGCUGCCAGGAAACUACUUUCCAGAGAAAAACAGCCCCCCAUAGACAACAUAAUCCGGGCUGGUUUGAUUCCGAAAUUUGUGUCCUUCUUGGGCAGAACUGAUUGUAGUCCCAUUCAGUUUGAAUCUGCUUGGGCACUCACUAACAUUGCUUCUGGGACAUCAGAACAAACCAAGGCUGUGGUAGAUGGAGGUGCCAUCCCAGCAUUCAUUUCUCUGUUGGCAUCUCCCCAUGCUCACAUCAGUGAACAAGCUGUCUGGGCUCUAGGAAACAUUGCAGGUGAUGGCUCAGUGUUCCGAGACUUGGUUAUUAAGUACGGUGCAGUUGACCCACUGUUGGCUCUCCUUGCAGUUCCUGAUAUGUCAUCUUUAGCAUGUGGCUACUUACGUAAUCUUACCUGGACACUUUCUAAUCUUUGCCGCAACAAGAAUCCUGCACCCCCGAUAGAUGCUGUUGAGCAGAUUCUUCCUACCUUAGUUCGGCUCCUGCAUCAUGAUGAUCCAGAAGUAUUAGCAGAUACCUGCUGGGCUAUUUCCUACCUUACUGAUGGUCCAAAUGAACGAAUUGGCAUGGUGGUGAAAACAGGAGUUGUGCCCCAACUUGUGAAGCUUCUAGGAGCUUCUGAAUUGCCAAUUGUGACUCCUGCCCUAAGAGCCAUAGGGAAUAUUGUCACUGGUACAGAUGAACAGACUCAGGUUGUGAUUGAUGCAGGAGCACUCGCCGUCUUUCCCAGCCUGCUCACCAACCCCAAAACUAACAUUCAGAAGGAAGCUACGUGGACAAUGUCAAACAUCACAGCCGGCCGCCAGGACCAGAUACAGCAAGUUGUGAAUCAUGGAUUAGUCCCAUUCCUUGUCAGUGUUCUCUCUAAGGCAGAUUUUAAGACACAAAAGGAAGCUGUGUGGGCCGUGACCAACUAUACCAGUGGUGGAACAGUUGAACAGAUUGUGUACCUUGUUCACUGUGGCAUAAUAGAACCGUUGAUGAACCUCUUAACUGCAAAAGAUACCAAGAUUAUUCUGGUUAUCCUGGAUGCCAUUUCAAAUAUCUUUCAGGCUGCUGAGAAACUAGGUGAAACUGAGAAACUUAGUAUAAUGAUUGAAGAAUGUGGAGGCUUAGACAAAAUUGAAGCUCUACAAAACCAUGAAAAUGAGUCUGUGUAUAAGGCUUCGUUAAGCUUAAUUGAGAAGUAUUUCUCUGUAGAGGAAGAGGAAGAUCAAAACGUUGUACCAGAAACUACCUCUGAAGGCUACACUUUCCAAGUUCAGGAUGGGGCUCCUGGGACCUUUAACUUUUAGAUCAUGUAGCUGAGACAUAAAUUUGUUGUGUACUACGUUUGGUAUUUUGUCUUAUUGUUUCUCUACUAAGAACUCUUUCUUAAAUGUGGUUUGUUACUGUAGCACUUUUUACACUGAAACUAUACUUGAACAGUUCCAACUGUACAUACAUACUGUAUGAAGCUUGUCCUCUGACUAGGUUUCUAAUUUCUAUGUGGAAUUUCCUAUCUUGCAGCAUCCUGUAAAUAAACAUUCAAGUCCACCCUUUUCUUGACUUCA